CAUUACCGCGCAGGCUUGGUCACCGCAUUAAGGCAUUCCCGCUCUCCGCGGAACUGCUCUGCCGUCUCGGCGGUGAAAGUGUGAGAGGGUCCGUAGUUGGGUCAACUUUGACUCCUCUCGCCUGCCCGGAUCCUUAAGGGCCUCCUCGUCCUCCCGGUCUCCGGUCGCUGCCGGGUCUGUGCGCCGGUCCGCGCCCGCCCUCGCUCUGCCAUGGGCGCUUCCAGCUCCUCCGCGCUGGCCCGCCUCGGCCUCCCAGCCCGGCCCUGGCCCAGGUGGCUCGGGGUCGCCGCGCUAGGACUGGCCGCCGUGGCCCUGGGGACUGUCGCCUGGCGCCGCGCAUGGCCCAGGCGGCGCCGGCGGCUGCAGCAGGUGGGCACCGUGGCGAAGCUCUGGAUCUACCCGGUGAAAUCCUGCAAAGGGGUGCCGGUGAGCGAGGCUGAGUGCACGGCCAUGGGGCUGCGCAGCGGCAACCUGCGGGACAGGUUUUGGCUGGUGAUUAAGGAAGAUGGACACAUGGUCACUGCCCGACAGGAGCCUCGCCUCGUGCUCAUCUCCAUCAUUUAUGAGAAUAACUGCCUGAUCUUCAGGGCUCCAGACAUGGACCAGCUGGUUUUGCCUAGCAAGCAGCCUUCCUCAAACAAACUCCACAACUGCAGGAUAUUUGGCCUUGACAUUAAAGGCAGAGACUGUGGCAAUGAGGCAGCUAAGUGGUUCACCAACUUCUUGAAAACUGAAGCGUAUAGAUUGGUUCAAUUUGAGACAAACAUGAAGGGAAGAACAUCAAGAAAACUUCUCCCCACUCUUGAUCAGAAUUUCCAGGUGGCCUACCCAGACUACUGCCCGCUCCUGAUCAUGACAGAUGCCUCCCUGGUAGAUUUGAAUACCAGGAUGGAGAAGAAAAUGAAAAUGGAGAAUUUCAGGCCAAAUAUUGUGGUGACCGGCUGUGAUGCUUUUGAGGAGGAUACCUGGGAUGAACUCCUAAUUGGUAGUGUAGAAGUGAAAAAGGUAAUGGCAUGCCCCAGGUGUAUUUUGACAACGGUGGACCCAGACACUGGAGUCAUAGACAGGAAACAGCCACUGGACACCCUGAAGAGCUACCGCCUGUGUGAUCCUUCUGAGAGGGAAUUGUACAAGUUGUCUCCACUUUUUGGGAUCUAUUAUUCAGUGGAAAAAAUUGGAAGCCUGAGAGUUGGUGACCCUGUGUAUCGGAUGGUGUAGUGAUGAGUGAUGGAUCCACUAGGGUGAUAUGGUAAAGGGCUUCAGCAACCAGGAGGGAUUGACUGAGAUCUUAACAACAGCAGCAACGAUACAUCAGCAAAUCCUUAUUAUCCAGCCUUCAACUAUCUUUACCCUGGAAAACAAUCUCGAUUUUUGACUUUUCAAAGUUGUGUAUGCUCCAGGUUAAUGCAAGGAAAGUAUUAGAGGGGGGAAUAUGAAAGUAUAUAUAUAAAUUUUAGGUACUGAAGGCUUUAAAAAUAAUUAAGAUCAUCAAAAAUGCUAUUUUGAAUGUUAUCAUGGCUAUUACACUUUUACUUCCUGACUUUAAUAUUGAUGAAUAAAGCAAGUUUAAUGAAUCAACUAAAAAGCUGCAAAAAUGUUUUUAAAAUGUGUGCCUUUUAUUACCUAUCAGUCUAUGUUUUGGGAGAAAUGGGAAGCAACAGAUCACUGUGUCCUGAUGUGCAGGACGCAUGUUACCACACUCACAAAUGCCUAAUAUUGGUCUUUAUGUGGCCAUUGAGUCCUGUUGACUUUCCACUCAUGUGCUUUUUACUCUAGCAUUAUGGAAUCUGGGCUGUACUUGAGUAUGGAAAUUCUCUUAUAGACUUAGUUUUAGUACUCUAUUACACCUUUACUAAGCCACAUAAAAGUAAUCUGUUUGUGUGUAACUGCCAGAUAUACCACCUGGAAUUCCAAGUAAGAUAAGGAAGAGGAUGACAUUUAAAAGAGAAUGGAAUUUUGAGAGUAGGAAUGCAAGGAAGACAGCAUGAACAUAUUUUUUUCAGUGCAAAUAAUUUUUUCGUAACAAAGAAACGAACAACUUUGGUAUGAUCUUAAGCAAAAAUACUCACUGAAAUAGUAUGUGGAUGAAUUCACCUACUUACAAUUUUAUGGUUUCUUUGUAAAUAAUAAAUGUGAAUCUCAAUCCUGCUUUA